CCCAAGACCUACAUGGAAUAAUCAAGAAAGUCAUAGAGACAUUAAUCAAGAUCAUCAAAUUGUUGGAUGGAAAACGAUCUCAAACUGUGGGAAUCUUGAUAUCUAGUUUACAUUUAGAAAUGAAGGAUAUCCAACAGGCCAUUUUCAAUGUGGAUGACUCCGUGGUUGAUCUGGAGACCCUGGCAGCCUUAUAUGAAAACAGAGCCCAAGAGGAUGAGCUGGUUAAAAUAAGAAAGUAUUACGAGACAUCCAAAGAAGAAGAACUGAAGCUGCUGGAUAAACCUGAGCAAUUUUUACAUGAGUUAGCCCAGAUUCCUAAUUUUGCUGAACGUGCCCAGUGCAUAAUCUUCAGAUCUGUCUUUUCUGAGGGUAUCACCUCCUUGCACAGAAAGGUAGAGAUCAUCACGCGAGCUUCUAAGGACUUGCUGCACGUGAAGAGCGUGAAGGAUAUUUUAGCUCUCAUCUUGGCUUUUGGAAAUUAUAUGAAUGGAGGAAAUAGGACUCGGGGACAAGCCGAUGGAUAUAGCUUAGAAAUUCUGCCCAAACUCAAGGAUGUCAAAAGUCGGGAUAAUGGGAUUAAUCUGGUGGACUACGUUGUUAAGUAUUACCUGCGUUACUAUGAUCAGGAAGCUGGAACAGAAAAGAGUGUUUUCCCCUUGCCGGAACCACAGGAUUUCUUUCUGGCCUCCCAAGUCAAGUUUGAAGACCUCAUAAAAGAUUUGAGAAAACUGAAGAGGCAACUAGAAGCAAGUGAGAAACAGAUGGUGGUGGUGUGCAAGGAGUCCCCAAAGGAGUAUCUCCAGCCUUUCAAGGACAAACUAGAGGAGUUCUUCCAAAAAGCCAAAAAAGAGCAUAAGAUGGAAGAAAGUCACUUGGAGAAUGCACAGAAAAGUUUUGAAACAACAGUACGAUAUUUUGGGAUGAAGCCAAAGUCUGGUGAGAAGGAGAUCACACCCAGCUACGUGUUUAUGGUGUGGUAUGAGUUCUGCAGUGACUUCAAGACAAUUUGGAAACGGGAGAGUAAAAACAUAUCUAAAGAAAGAUUGAAAAUGGCUCAGGAAUCAGUCAGCAAGUUGACUUCAGAGAAGAAAGUGGAGACAAAGAAAAUCAAUCCCACUGCUAGCCUGAAAGAAAGACUGCGUCAGAAGGAAGCCAGUGUGACCACUAACUAAGAUGAAGACACAUGGAAAUGAUGGCACUGGAGGUGGAGGACCUUGCACGCAUACUCUUUGUGACCACAGGGUUGCAGGACGUUCUUGAAAGAUGUGUCACUAAAUGUUUGUUUUUGCUCAUCUCUUUCUGAGGUCAUCUGCAGAGAGUGCCCCAUGCCUUCUUUAAGAAGUCCCUCAUUAAGCCGCAGGAACAAUGGAAAACUAUUUAAGGGAACAUUGCAGAAAUAUUUGAUGACUGUUUCUUGUGGAAGCCCAAAGUCCACUCUAAGAGCAGAAGAAAUACCAAAAUGUUUCCAAAAUUUUUUUAAAAGCUGAGAUUUCCAGCUUUAUAACCAAAGCUUGAUAUAUGUCACAUUGUCACAGAAGAGAGAAAAGAUCAUUGAGGACAGUUGCCUUGGGAGAGUUCAAGUCUUUGUCGUUACACACUGCUGUUUUGAUUAUUGGUCUUAGUUUUGAUCCUGUUGCAGCAAAAUCCUGCAGCAUCUUUCUCUCCAAUAAUGUUGCAACUCACCAAAACUAUUCUUGAAGAGGUCCAAGAACAUGUAUUAUCCAGACUAAAAAAAUGAUUUUUUGUUGUUAUGGUUUACGUGAUGAAAAGGAGAAAAAACAGAAUCAUACCUGGGUGGAGAGAGGGAGACAAAUAGCCAUAAACUUCAUCCUGGAGAACAAGUUACCAUGCAAGGAGUUGACAUCAGUUGUUCAGUGAGGCCCAUUCUUGUUUUUACAUCGGUCCUUUGUGGUUUUUCUGGGCCAGCAGAGAUUCUGCACCCCAACUCCCAGGAGAAAAUGUAAUACCUGAGCAAGCACAGCCUUGGGUGUGCUUGGACAAGAGACCCAGCGGCAGAGCACCUUUUACAUUUUGGACCGUUCAUGAAUGGACAAUGUUGUGUUGAUACGCAGCCGAGUUCUACGUUAUGUGCUGUGACUGUGCAGCUGGACGACCCCCAUCCCCAGGAGGCAGUUUCCAGACAGGAGAGCAAAUGCAACUCACAGCACCUGCUCAUGACCUUGGCUGAUAGGCAUGUGAAGUAGGAUGAAGCAGGACUCUUUAAUGUCAAAAAAACUGAAGGGCAGAAAAAAGGUUCCUUACAUCAAAAUGAAAGUAAUUACAUUAAUAGAAAACUUCCAAGUGGAAUAUUGUUCACAGGCAGCUCUUUCUGACCCUGGCUCUUGAGUCACAUAAGGAAACCACCUUUGACCUCUCUGACACUUUUGUCUUUAAGCCACGUCUCUGAAAUCUUGUGAGGGGUGAAGAAAGAGGACUGGAGAUGAAUGGACAAUAUGAUCAAAGACUCAUUUUUAGGCCUUGAAGAGGCCGAGCUUUCUCCCCCCAAUUGGUGGAGGACAGUCCAGAGAUGAGCAGAAAUCUUAAAUUCCUUCCUGAUCCAGCCUCCACAUGUGGCCUGCCCCUUGCCCCAGCAUCUUUCCAGAACCCCUGGACUUGCCAGGUGCCUGAGCAUCUUCCCAGGAUAUGCCUGCCAGCCAGCAGCCCCUCAGGAAUGCUUCUAUAAUAGAUCCAGUAAUGAAAGCAGCACCAUAUCCUAAUCUAAUGUCAGCUUCGAGAAUGAAGACUGCAGUCAGGAUCAAAUCAAGUCACAGAAGCCAUAUUCAUGCAGGUGCUAACCGCCUUUUCUACUGGUGCAACUGAAAGGAAUAUGGUAACAUGGUUGGAUUUUUAAAAUUCACAAUGAAGGAACGAGACAAGCAAAACAGAAAAGCCGAGAAGGAACAUGCAUGACUAAAAAGGCUUGAAGUUGCUUGUGAGCAACAAGCUUUUUAUGCUGCUUUCUUACAUAGUUUCUCUUCAUUUUCACUUAACUCUGAAGACAACCAAAAGAACGGAUCAAUUAAAAACUAAUUCCACUUAUAACCAUCAUAUGCUCCUUCUAGUGUUAUCAUGCACAAGAAAAGUGCCAGUUUUACCCAUGCCAUAGAAAUCAGCUCUUUUGAGUUACAUGGGGCCAGCAGAAGUCUCAAUCCUUAUAGGCUUGAUGGUGAGAGCAGCGGGAGGUUUGAGGUGUACUCAUUGCAGUCCAGUUUGGUCUCUAAAUAGGAUGCUUACGAGAAAUCAGUGAAGGUAAGCAGGGCUGCCACUGUGGCCACGUAACCCUUCAGGAACCAGUGCUGAAGAAUAAUGAGUGAGAACACUUAAUUUGAGAGUUAGACAAAUACAGCCCACUUUGGAUUUCAUCCUAGUGAACAGACUAAAACUUUGCAGUAAAAUACCUAUUUCUACAAAGCAAGGUUUGCCUGCCUCGGUUGGGGAAACCUAGUGGUUUUGUCACACUAGUCGAUGUAUGAUGUUAGUGUUGUAAGACACCAUGGCAGAAUCUUCAUUAUUCUCACCUAUUCUGAACCCUGCGUCAUGUAUCUGGGAUGCCCCCUCCCAAGUCCACCAAUGUACCACGUUGCUGACACAGCCUUCAUUUUUAACUCAAAUUGAUGCUCAGUAAAGGUCAAUGACAAUUUGUUCAAGGAAGUUCAUCUAAAAUAAUCUGGAGGCCUUGAAAAUGAUCCCUCUAAAAUGCUGUUGAGCUUGUGUUCAGUGUAGCAGGAGGAUCUGAACUUUUCCUGGAGAGGAGGUGAUCGGGAUGCCAUUUGGCAGCUUAAGCACAUCCUGCCAGCAGGCUUUAAGUGGCUGUUCUAGGCAUAGCCCUCCCUGAACUAGAAAGGAGAGUAACCAGUUUGCUAUGCUGCGUCUCACCAGACACACCUGACUUAGUAGUAACUCUAAGAACCCUUAACUUACAAACAACUUUGUCUCCUCUUAGACAAUAUUCAUUAAAUCUGAGGACACAGUUUGACAGUAGUUCAGAUUCUUGCAUGAGCAAUUGACAGCAUCAGAGCACACAAUAUCAUAAGUUACAUAAAUUACACAAAGUACAUCAUAAAUUACACUACAGACACAUUAGGUAAAAAGCAUCAGGCCCGGGCCGGGCGUGGUGGCUCAUGCCUAUAAUCCCAGCACUUUGGGAGGCCAAGCAGGGGCGGAUCACGAGGUCAGGAGAUUGAGACCAUCCUGGCUAACACGGUGAAACCCCAUCUCUACUAAAAAUACAAAAAAUUAGCCGGGCGUGGUGGUGGGCGCCUGUAGUCCCAGCUACUCGGGAGGCUGAGGCAGGAGAAUGGCGUGAACCCGGGAGGUGGAGCUUGCAGCUAGCCGAGAUCGCGCCACUGCACUCCAGCCUGGGCGACAGUGAGACUCCGUUUCAAAAAAAAAAAGCAUCAGGCCCAUGAAGUAUCAAAAACCAGGUUAGGAGGUGUGCUGUAUGGCUUUUAUCUCAAGAAGUGGCAGCUUACUGGGGAAAAAGAAAUAAGAAAAAGUGUGGCCAAGCAGAAGUGGAUGUUUAUGAUGACGGUGGGGGCCCAGAAGUCAUAGGUGAUGGUCCUACUGCCCAACAGUUGCCUUUUGAAUCCUUAUGUUGAUGAUGGUGUCUUUCUACACACUCACUGCAACUACUCAGGAAUUAUAAAGAUUUUCUGAAAUCUGAGAAGUGGAAUAAGGAAACCCAGUGGAGCUAUUACACUUUUAAAUGUUCUAGCCAAAACAAAUUGCCAGUAUGGUUGAGGAAUUGAAUAUCAGAUGGCAUGCAGUCUCCCCUCCCCUCCCCUAUCAAGGACAGUAGAAGCUGCAAACCUCUUCUCAGCCUCCUUCAGGCACCUCCUGUUUUCAUAAGCACCAUGAAGAAUGGUGUUUCCUAAAUGAAAAGUUCAGAUACUGCUGGUAAAGAAACUGGAAAAACUGAAGGAAGGAAUAAAAUAUGUUGGUGGUAUUAACACCUCCAGUAAGAUAAGUCAUUGGUACGGUUUUUCUAAGGGCCGCAGUGAGAUGUAGCAGAAGAAAUAUGUUUAUUUUGGGCAAAGAUUUGCUUAUUGGCCUGGGAUUGCACAUUUUCUCUAUGAUGUUUGCAACAGAGAAAUUUUCAUUUUAAUGAUACUCUUCCUUUCUUGAAAGUUACAUGUCCUCAUUUCUGUUUCUGCUUCUCCCUUGGCCAGUGUCAUUGAUGCAGAUCAUUGCAUACAACAGCACAGCAAAUUGCGCCAAGUCAGUGUGUGAAUGGGAAUUAGCAAUGCACGCUUGCAGGCUCUUUUUCCAGGAACCAGGCUGUAACAUUGACCGGGGAACCUCUUCAUUCCCUGACAUACUAAAUUGGUCAAUUUUGUAGUACUCAUCUCCAUCCACAAAAACAACAAAGAUAAAAUCAAUUUGGAGCUUUAUAUGACAAAAAGGAAGAAGUCCAAAAAUAUAUAGCCUUCCCCCCUCCCACAUAUCUGAUCCAAAUAUUAAAUAUCUGAUUUUAUAAAACAGUUUAAAUUGUCUUUUUAAAUUGCUAACAAGCAUCAGUUAUAUUUGAGCUUCAUUUUUCUUUUAUCCUGUCUGUCCUAAUAAAAACAAAAAUGGCCAAAAAGUGGAGAGGAAAGAAAAAGCUUCCACUUUUUAAAAUUUGUUUUGUAUUAGUUAUUUUACCUUUAGGGACCCUACAACUGAAGAGAGUGGAGAGAAUAAAGAAGUGAACUUUCAUUCAUGUCUGCUACUUUGACCUCAUAAAGAAAUCUGCAACACAGAUGAAACCAGUCUGUGUGGCCAAGCUGAUGGGAUUUGAAAAGAGUGGAUAAUUUUUAGCCUUUCCAAAAUGCAAAUAACUUGGAUAUAUUUCCAUUUUCCAGCUAUAGAGAGAAACAAUCCAGCUGCCUGGAAACUGUUAUUAGUAUAGAAGUGGCUUAAAGAAAAGCAUCUUCAAAUACUUGACUUAGCAUAUCUUUCUUCUUUAGACUUACAUAAUGAUAUUCAUCUCUCCAUUAGCAAUUGAAUCCAGGCAUAACCGGGCUCAGUUACACAGCUUGUCUGUGACUGGGAAGCCCAUUUUGUGUCAUUUCUGCACACCUGUCCGCUGUUGACACCUUAUUAGAGGCACUGCAUUUUGGUUUCACAAUUCUUCAUCUCCCUUCCCAAGGAAUGGGCAAUCUACUGAACUUCCAGAUCAAUGCUUUGUUGGAAAGUGAUGAAUUUAAGAGAGUUUUAACAUGUCAAAUUUGAAGCCAAUUCAGUAUCCUUAUUUGUUCCAAGACUCUUAACCAAUACUGUGAUAUAAAGUUAGGAUUUGGGAAACGUGUAGUUAACAACUUGGAAACAUGAAGAUAUUAAAAUGGCAGCUGGCUAACUGUCUCUUAAGCCACUAUGCAAUUUCUACCAAUGGAGAGAUUAGGGAAGCAAAUUAAGCCUCAUUCAGUAGGUCUGCUGUCUGGUGGAACUUACGGAACUCAUUUCCUCCUCUAUCCCCAGCCCUUCUCCUAACUAUGGUGAUAACCAGGGCCAUAGAAGACCUUUUCUCUCUUACCUUUCUCUGAUAGGAUCGUGUCCUUCAGUCAAGAGCUCAUGUGAACUCCAGACUUUAUAUUACAUCUCUGAAGUUCUUGAUGUGGGGAAGAUUGACUUUUAUUCCAUUUUUAUAUGAAGGUGUUAGAUAUAGCCAUCAAUUUAUUUUUCUACAUUCCCUCUACGCUUAUGUAAUUUUCUAUUUUUAAAUCUUCUCUUAAAUAUACUGAGAAUCUCUAGUCUCCUUUUCUAAAGGCUGAUCCAACUACACUUGUGGGCUAUUUUUCCAAGCUUUGUGUGAAACUUGAUGACAUUGGGCCAGCAAAAUGCAAAGAAGACUAUAGUUUCAGGCAGAAAAUCACGUCCAAAGAAUUUGGCAUGGAUUAAACAACCUCUACCACACUAUAGCUCUCACAUAGGCUGAACAUUUUCCUAAAUUCUACCUGUGCAGACACUGAGGGGCUCUCUACCUUUGAAACUAUGAGAACGUCUUAAAUUAAUAUGAAUAUUUCUCUCCAUGUAUAGUGUGAGCUGCCAAUGCAUUAUCUUAAUACAUCAAGAAGGAAAUCAGAUUUCAGGCACACAUUAGCAAUUGUUUGUUAAUGUCCUUGGCAAACGUGUACCUGCUUUCCUUCAUUGUUCUCUUCAGGGGCUUUCUUCCACUUUCCUCUUAUGAAACGAAUGUGUUUUUGACUGUUAACUGGGUUCGCUUUCCAGAUCUGUCUUUCCCAAAUGAAAGGUUAGUCCCAUAGACCACUGGCUAUUCAGGGAAAUUACUCUCUACCUCCCCAUGACAUGGAUGAUAAGUGUUGAGGGAUGAACACUCUGGAAACUCUUAGCAUGGAUUUUGAAUUCCAGAUUUCUUUAUAGGAGAUGUAUAAAAAGGAGUUUAUAGCAUACAAAAAUUAUACUGCUCUUCCCAGUAAGGGACUAAAAGGACAUUUGAAAUCUUUACAUUUUAGAUGUUUUUGUGAAUUAUAAAUAUCUCCUUUUUCCUCGCUUCAUGCUAACUUGUCUCUAGAUAAAAUCUUAUUUCUUCAUACAUUGGACCACAAGGCAUAAAGAAGGUAGCUCAGCGCCACUGAGAUUGUGUUCUGCAUAAUAUUUGGAAGGCUUCCAUUUCCAUUGAAAACAAAUCCAUGAGUGAGAGGGAAAGUCUAGUAUCAAUUCUUCUGUUUGCUCGCAAUGACACAAAUAGGUUUUGGGGAUCUACCUAAGGGAUAGGUCUACUCCAAAAUUAUUAAAUUUAUAAUUGUGCAAUUCUGUAAUUUCCCAAGGCAUAAGUAAUAUGACCCUACUGUCAGCUAGAUGUCUUAUCUUCAAAGAGAGUAUGCAUUAAUAAAAAGAACUUCCCUUUAAAGAACCAAUCUAAAAUACUAAAAAGGCAGAAACUUUUAAAAUUAGAAAUUGGAUAAUUUUUAAGAAUCUUUAGAGAAAACAUUGGUUUAUCAUAGUCUUUUUCUUUCAUUGAGUUUUCAUUUAGACUAGCAUGGCAAGCAGGGUGGCCUUGGACUUUGAUUUAGGGGAUCGUGCUUUGGCCUGGAAAAUAAGCACUGGCCUGCAUGCCUAGAACCUGAGUGAAGGCAGUCAACAUCCUAGUAUGAAUCAGACCUAGCAGAAAUGUAAAUUAUUUCAAGUACUUCAGGGUUUAGUUUUCUUAGUGACACCCUGGACCCUGGAUGCUGCUUUCUAAAGUGCACCUGAUCCAUGCAGUUUUAUGUCUUCAUAUAACUGGUAUCUUGUGAGUUUGCAAGCAAUGGGAUGAGCAAGAAAAAAAGGACGCAUGGAGGAGAAAAAUUUGAACGAGGCUAGUGCAAUGUUUUGCUGAUAGAUUACAUUGUUAGGGAGCUGGUGAUUUUUUGCCAUGGUCGUAUCGUGGACAGCUUUUCCGUGGAAAUUCAAGGCAUCUGUAUUAGGCAAAUGUGAGUGCCCUUGAUCUUGUAUUGAUCAGUGCCAAUGUACUGGGAAAGCAGGUACCCCAGUGAAACUGGUCUGUGCUUGGUUUAACAGCUCCAACAAUUUCAGAUCCAUGGGGCUGCUUGACCAUAGACCCUGUUUACUCCAUGCCUGUUCAAAAGUCAUUUUGACUUCUAGCUUUGUUUCACUUUCUUCUUUCAAUACUUCUGUUUCCUCGUCCUUUUCCUUCAUAUUCCAUGGCUAUUUCUUUCCUACUUUACAGUUUCCCCCAGACCCAGAUUUUUUCACACCUCUGCAUCAUAGACAACUGAGUAGCUCCCUUGGCCCCUCCUCCAUCCUCUCACACCCUGUGCUCCGUUCCUCAGCCGUUUGGACAGGGAGCUCCGCUGUCACCAAGGAGCCCAUGUGAGACACACUGCUGUGACUGCCUCUUGUUAAUGUCAGCAUCACCUCAUCACUUAAGCAAAAAGGAAAAUCCAUAAAAGAGAUGGAAAAUACGUCUCUUUUUAUUUUAUUUUAAGAAGAUUGGGCGGGGUGGGGGGGGGGUUCUUAUUCUAGGCCUUCUCAAUUUCUCAUAGAUUUUACCUUAAACUAAUUAAGGCCAUUCUCUUGAUAAAUUUGUACAUCAGACCGGGUCACCAGCUAUGAUGCAGAACGCCAGAUUUUUGAAUCUCAAGUAACUUUCUGUGGUGCUGGACAAAUUGACUUAAUUCUGUGCAGGCAAACACUUUGAAUCAUAAGGAUUUUUAUUGCCGCUCCAUUCUUACUACUAUUCAUGAUUCAAACAUCUACCCCUGUUCUGAAUCAGGAUGUUGACACUUCUUGGUUAUUUUCAGAUGAACAGUAACUGCUACACUCUUGAAAGCACUUAAAAGUGCAAGCAUGUCCUAAAUAGCCAUUUAACCUGGUAAAACAUAGGCUUUUCUGUUUAAUUAAGUAUUAGACCAGUCUGUAGAUAUAAUCUGAAAAGAUUGUAGGCAGUAAUGAAGACAGUUGGGGAAAGGAGAAGGCCCUUUAAAGACAUGAAACCUUACACGCUCUUGGGAUAUUUUUAAGCAUAAUAAGCUCAUUGGAUUCAGGUAUUUUUCCCUUUGCAUUUUUAAAAAUACGUAUUUCUAAUUUGUUUGCAUAUUUAAUUUUGUCAAAGCUGAGAAAUGCUCAUGAGUUGAAUUUAUAAAUGUCAUUUGCAACCAAAUGAAGUAUUUAUUUUUAAAAAGAGAGUGAAGGAACCAACACUGAUUUGUACAUAAUAAAAAUGUGUGUAUUAUAUAUAUAUAUUUUUUCCUCCUUGACAGUACUUGGUCACAAUAUCAAGUGUAUUUUUGUACAUAAUAUAUAUUGAUUAGAAAAACGUCAAUUGUCUAUUCAAAAAAUUCUAUCUCUGUGAUAGAUUAUAUUUAUCCUAAUCUGUUGAUACCUCUGUUAAUUUGUUUUAAGAGAAUUAUAUUUUUUGGAAUUUACAGAGAAUUGCAUUCAUGGCUUUCAAUUGUAAAUAUGCUAAGGGUAUUUUAAUAAAUCUUGGUUUCAUGUCCA